AGCGUCCCCCACACCACAGACCCGCGCCGCCGACGACCCAGCAGCCGCCAUGGCUCUGCUCCGAGGUGUGUUUGUAGUUGCUGCUAAGCGAACGCCCUUUGGAGCUUACGGAGGCCUUCUGAAAGACUUCACUGCUACUGACUUGUCUGAAUUUGCUGCCAAGGCUGCCUUGUCUGCUGGCAAAGUCUCACCUGAAACAGUUGACAGUGUGAUUAUGGGCAAUGUCCUGCAGAGUUCUUCAGAUGCUAUAUAUUUGGCAAGGCAUGUUGGUUUGCGUGUGGGAAUCCCAAAGGAGACCCCAGCUCUCACGAUUAAUAGGCUCUGUGGUUCUGGUUUUCAGUCCAUUGUGAAUGGAUGUCAGGAAAUUUGUGUUAAAGAAGCUGAAGUUGUUUUAUGUGGAGGAACCGAAAGCAUGAGCCAAGCUCCCUACUGUGUCAGAAAUGUGCGUUUUGGAACCAAGCUUGGAUCAGAUAUCAAGCUGGAAGAUUCUUUAUGGGUAUCAUUAACAGAUCAGCAUGUCCAGCUCCCCAUGGCAAUGACUGCAGAGAAUCUUGCUGUAAAACACAAAAUAAGCAGAGAAGAAUGUGACAAAUAUGCCCUGCAGUCACAGCAGAGAUGGAAAGCUGCUAAUGAUGCUGGCUACUUUAAUGAUGAAAUGGCACCAAUUGAAGUGAAGACAAAGAAAGGAAAACAGACAAUGCAGGUAGACGAGCAUGCUCGGCCCCAAACCACCCUGGAACAGUUACAGAAACUUCCUCCAGUAUUCAAGAAAGAUGGAACUGUUACUGCAGGGAAUGCAUCGGGUGUAGCUGAUGGUGCUGGAGCUGUUAUCAUAGCUAGUGAAGAUGCUGUUAAGAAACAUAACUUCACACCACUGGCAAGAAUUGUGGGCUACUUUGUAUCUGGAUGUGAUCCCUCUAUCAUGGGUAUUGGUCCUGUCCCUGCUAUCAGUGGGGCACUGAAGAAAGCAGGACUGAGUCUUAAGGACAUGGAUUUGGUAGAGGUGAAUGAAGCUUUUGCUCCCCAGUACUUGGCUGUUGAGAGGAGUUUGGAUCUUGACAUAAGUAAAACCAAUGUGAAUGGAGGAGCCAUUGCUUUGGGUCACCCACUGGGAGGAUCUGGAUCAAGAAUUACUGCACACCUGGUUCACGAAUUAAGGCGUCGAGGUGGAAAAUAUGCCGUUGGAUCAGCUUGCAUUGGAGGUGGCCAAGGUAUUGCUGUCAUCAUUCAGAGCACAGCCUGAAGAGACCAGUGAGCUCACUGUGACCCAUCCUUACUCUACUUGGCCAGGCCACAGUAAAACAAGUGACCUUCAGAGCAGCUGCCACAACUGGCCAUGCCCUGCCAUUGAAACAGUGAUUAAGUUUGAUCAAGCCAUGGUGACACAAAAAUGCAUUGAUCAUGAAUAGGAGCCCAUGCUAGAAGUACAUUCUCUCAGAUUUGAACCAGUGAAAUAUGAUGUAUUUCUGAGCUAAAACUCAACUAUAGAAGACAUUAAAAGAAAUCGUAUUCUUGCCAAGUAACCACCACUUCUGCCUUAGAUAAUAUGAUUAUAAGGAAAUCAAAUAAAUGUUGCCUUAACUUCAGUUAAUAUUUUCCUGUCAUUUAUAUUUUUAAAAAUUUUAAAUUGUGAUAAGAUACACAUUACAUAAACUUUACCAUCUUAACCCUUUUUUAGCGUACAAUUCACUGGUAUUAAGUACAUUCACAUUUUUAUACAAACAUCCCCACUUUUUAUCAACAGAACUUUUUCAGUCACCACACAUGGAAACAAUAACUCCUGAUUCUCCCAUCCCCCAUCCCCUGACAACCACCAGUGUAUUUUGUUUCUAUAAAUUUGAUGACUCGAGGUACCUCAUAAGUGAAAUUAUAAAUAUCUGUCCUUUCGUGACUGGCUUAUUUUACUUUACUUUAUAUAAUGUUCUCAAGAUUCAUCCACCUUAUGGUGUAGCAUGUGUCAGAAUUUCCUUCUUUUUAAAGGCUGAAUAAUAUUCUGCUGUGUGUAUAAACCUUACUUCCUUCUUCCCAGCUUAAAGGCCAUCUUUCAUCCUUUAUUUUCUCCCUUUAAAAUGCCCCCACAACACUUCCAUUGCUUUAUUUGUCUGUUCUAAGACUGGAUAUCUAGUAGGGCAAGGCCCUAUUCUUGUUAACUUCAUCAAAGAGCCACUGGAAAUUUUAAUUAAGAUUAAAUUGAAUUUAUGGGUUAUACAUUUAUUGGGGGGAAAUUUUUUUUUUUUUUUUUGAGACAGAGUCUCGCUCUGUCCUCCAGGCUGGAGUGCAGUGGCGCGAUCUCAGCUUACUGCAAGCUCCGCCUCCUGGGUUCAUGCCAUUCUCCUGCCUCAGCCUCCCCAGUAGCUGGGACUACAGGCGCCUGCCACUACGCCCGGCUAAUUUUUUGUAUUUUUAGUAGAGAUGGGGUUUCACCGUGUUAGCCAGGAUGGUCUCGAUCUCCUGACCUCGUGAUCCACCCGCCUCGGCCUCCCAAAGAAGUGCUGGGAUUACAGGCGUGAGCCACUGCACCCGGCCUUUUUUUUUUUUUUUUGAGAUAGCAUCUUGCUCUGUCACCCAGGCAGAAUUGCAGUGGCACAGUCAUGGCUCACUGAAUAAUAGAUGUUAAAUAAUACUAGAUGUUAAAUAAUAGUAUCAUAAGUACCUACACUGUUUCCUCAACCCUUUGCUUAUAUGGUUUCCUUCAUUUGAUUAAAAAGCUGAAGUGGCACAUACAUCCCCCUUUCUGUCAUAGAGAGGCAGAUGACAAGCGGCCUACCCACGGUUUGGGAUAAUGGACUAGUGGCAACAGGCAAGUCCAGCUUUUAUUGUUUGGGAUCCUUACUGAGAAGCAGCAGGCUUCCUCUACUGUCAUAAAAAUAUUAAAAAGUAAGAGCCCUGUAUAAUUUCUCAUAAUAAAACAAUGUUUUGCAGAACA